AGUUUGUUGAAGUUCGUGACUGCUUCACUCUCUCAUUCUUAGCUUGAAUUUGGAAAUGACUUUUGAUGACCUAAAGAUCCAGACUGUGAAGGACCAGCCUGAUGAGAAGUCAAAUGGAAAAAAAGCUAAAGAAUCUUGGUUAGAUCGGUACCUACUGCAAAGAAUCGGAUUGGUUUAUGAUUGGAAAAUCACUAGUAGGGGCAGCAGUUGGAUUAAUGGUCUCUGCCUACCAAGGACACAGGACAAAGAGAAUCUAUAGAAAAAGGGAACACAUACCUUCCUUCACAGGGUCCUGUGAUUUUCUUUUUCCUCUAAAAAUUUAGUUUUUCAUUAUUUAAGAGUGAUGAGGCCAGGCGCGGUGGCUCACGCCUGUAAUCCCAGCACUUUGGGAGGCUGAGGUGGGCGGAUCAUGAGGUCAGGAGUUCGAGACCAGCACGGUGAAACCUCAUCUGUACUAAAAAUACAAAAUUUAACCUGCUGUGGUGGUGCGCGGCUGCAAUCCCAGCUGCUCAGGAGGCUGAGGCAGGAGAAUCACUCGAACCCAGGAGGCGGAGGUUGCAGUGACCUGAGAUGGCGCCAUGGCACUCCAGCCUGGGCGAAGAGCAAGCUCCCCCUCAAAAAAAAAAAAAAAAAAAAGAGCACGAUGAGGGUAUCUGAUGCCCUACAAUGUGGAAUGAACAGUGACCACAGAGUUGAAAGAUUUACAUAGAGGUAUUUGCCCCUGAGGCUAGAAUUAGGCAAUUAUUUGCAAGAGACACAGCUAUCUUCUACAACUUCUCUGCUAGCUUGCCACACACACUCUAGAAGCCAGUCUUCAGUUUCUUUACUCUCCAUGGUGGUGCCUGGCUGCUGCGACUCUAGGGGUCCUUUGCCUGGGAUUAGUAGUGACCAUUAUGGUGCUGGGCAUGCAAUUAUCCCAGGUGUCUGACCUCCUAACACAAGAGCAAGCAAACCUAACUCACCAGAAAAAGAAACUGGAGGGACAGAUCUCAGCCCGGCAACAAGCAGAAGAAGCUUCACAGGAGUCAGAAAACGAACUCAAGGAAAUGAUAGAAACCCUUGCUCGGAAGCUGAAUGAGAAAUCCAAAGAGCAAAUGGAACUUCACCACCAGAAUCUGAAUCUCCAAGAAACACUGAAGAGAGUAGCAAAUUGUUCAGCUCCUUGUCCGCAAGACUGGAUCUGGCAUGGAGAAAACUGUUACCUAUUUUCCUCGGGCUCAUUUAACUGGGAAAAGAGCCAAGAGAAGUGCUUGUCUUUGGAUGCCAAGUUGCUGAAAAUUAAUAGCACAGCUGAUCUGGACUUCAUCCAGCAAGCAAUUUCCUAUUCCAGUUUUCCAUUCUGGAUGGGGCUGUCUCGGAGGAACCCCAGCUACCCAUGGCUCUGGGAGGACGGUUCUCCUUUGAUGCCCCACUUAUUUAGAGUCCGAGGCGCUGUCUCCCAGACAUACCCUUCAGGUACCUGUGCAUAUAUACAACGAGGAGCUGUUUAUGCGGAAAACUGCAUUUUAGCUGCCUUCAGUAUAUGUCAGAAGAAGGCAAACCUAAGAGCACAGUGAAUUUGAAGGCUCUGGAAGAAAAGAAAAAAGUCUUUGAGUUUUAUUCUGGAAUUUAAGCUAUUCUUUGUCACUUGGGUGCCAAACAUGAGAGCCCAGAAAACUGUCAUUUAGCUGGCUGCAGAACUCCUUUGCAGAAACUGGGGUUCCAGGAGCCUGGCACCUUUAUGUCAACAUUUUUGAUUCUAGCUACCUGUAUUAUUUCACCUAGCUUGUCCCAAGCUUCCCUGCCAGCCUGAAGUCCAUUUUCCCCUUUUUAUUUUAAAAUUUGACUCCUCUUCAAGCUUGAAAACCCUCUGAACUCAGUCUUCUUUACCUCAUUAUCACCUUCCCCUCACACUCCUAAAAUUGCAUGAAAGACAGAACAUGGAGAACUUGCUCAAGUGCAGGCAGAGAGCAAAAAGGGGAAAUAUGUCUGGGAAAAAGUGCACGUGAAGAAACAAAGAAGGACAGAGGCCAUUCCGAAAUCAAGAAACUCAUGUUCUUAACUUUAAAAAAGGUAUCAAUCCUUGGUUUUUAAACUGUGGUCCAUCUCCAGACUCUACCACUUACGGACAGACAGACAGACAGACACACACACACACACACACACACAUUUUGGGACAAGUGGGGAGCCCAAGAAAGUAAUUAGUAAGUGAGUGGUCUUUUCUGUAAGCUAAUCCACAACCUGUUACCACUUCCUGAAUCAGUUAUUAUUUCUUCAUUUUUUUUUCUACCAGAGGACAGAUUAAUAGAUUUAACCCUUCACAACAGUUCUUGUUAGAAUCAUGGGAUGUGUGGCCCAGAGGUAAGAAUAGAAUUUCUUUCCCUAAAGAACAUACCUUUUGUAGAUGAACUCUUCUCAACUCUGUUUUGCUAUGCUAUAAUUCCGAAACAUACAAGACAAAAAAAAUGAAGACACUCAAUCUAGAACAAACUAAGCCAGGUAUGCAAAUAUCGCUGAAUAGAAACAGAUGGAAUUAGAAAUAUAUCUUCUAUUUUUAGGCUUCUAUUUCCUUUCCACCCACUCUUCACAGGCUAUUCUACUUUAAAGGAAGCCUUUUUAUUUUGCUGCACACAAUCUAGCAGGAAUCUUUUUUUUUUUUUAAGAGCUGUGUCAUCCUUAUGUAGGCAAGAGAUGUUUGCUUUUGUUAAAAGCUUUAUUGAGAUAUAAUUAACAUAAAAUAAACUGAACAUAUUUAAAGUGUACUAUUUGAUAAGUUUUCACACCUUGUGGAGAACAUGCAUACUACAAUUAAGAGAGUGAACAUAUCCAUCAUCCCUCAAAGUGUCACAAUGCUCCUCCUGAUGACUCCUCCCCAGAAAACCACCAAUCGGCUUUCAUUUUGCAUUUUGUAGUUUUAUGUGAAUGGAAUCAUAUAGUAUGUCUUUUUUUUUUGUCUGGCUUCUUUCACUUUGCAUAAUUAUUUUGAGAUUCAUAUGUCUCCAUCUUGAUGCUCGUAUGAAUUCAUUCUUUUAAAUGUUGAAUAUUCCCUUGUAUGGAUAUACCACAAUUCAUUUACCCAUUUACUUGUUGAUGACAUUUGGGUUGUUUUAGUUUUGGGAUAUUACAAAUAAAGCUGCUGUGAACAUUUGUGUACAA